GACAAAUGGCUCAGGUGGACUCCGGGCUGGAGCUGUCCUGGGGGAGCUUGUUUGCGGCAGCGGCUGCUGCUGCCACUGCUGUGCUGGGGGCCCGGUCGCCAGGCAAAAAGCCCUCCCACGUUUGAGGGGAGUCAUGAGCCGUUUCCUGAAUGUGUUAAGAAGUUGGCUGGUUAUGGUGUCCAUCAUAGCCAUGGGGAACACGCUGCAGAGCUUCCGAGACCACACUUUUCUCUAUGAAAAGCUCUACACUGGCAAGCCAAACCUUGUGAAUGGCCUCCAAGCUCGGACCUUUGGGAUCUGGACGCUGCUCUCAUCAGUGAUUCGCUGCCUCUGUGCCAUUGACAUUCACAACAAGACGCUCUAUCACAUCACACUCUGGACCUUCCUCCUUGCCCUGGGGCAUUUCCUCUCUGAGUUGUUUGUCUAUGGAACUGCAGCUCCCACGAUUGGCGUCCUGGCACCCCUGAUGGUGGCAAGUUUCUCCAUCCUGGGUAUGCUGGUCGGGCUCCGGUAUCUAGAAGUAGAACCAGUAUCCAGACAGAAGAAGAGAAACUGAGGCCAGCAUUAUCACCUCCAGGACUUUCUCGUUUUCCACCUUGGCCAUCUUCUUCCUUCGUCGUCUCUCCUCUUUAAUUUCUUUUCUAUUCCAUCAUCUGCCCUUUUAUUCACUUUUAGCCUCUUUUUUUAAUUUUUAAAAUUUAAAGAUAUGCAUACUGAAAAGUAUAUAACAUGUACGUACAAUUUAAAGAAUAAUUUUAAAGUGAAUACUACGUAACUCCAUCCAAGUCAAGAAAUUGCCAGCUUCUCGGAAGCCCACUGUGUCUCCUUCCCCUACCUGCAACCUCUUCCAGGCUCCCUUUUCCAGCCUUCCCCUUUUUCCCUUUUAUUUUCAUGCCUUGAUUUGACUUGUGUGGUGGGAACAUGUGAACUAUGAAACUUAAACCUGCUGCCCACCCAGAGCAGCUGUGACCAAGGGCUGCCUCAAGGGGUUGUCCACGCAGGUUGGGCUCCUCUCUGCUGCUGGACCCAAGACUCUGAACCUUCCAAGGGACAGGCAGUUCUUCUAAGAAGGGCUCCCCUGUGUGUGAGCAAGACCACAGCUCUCCUUCUAUCUACAGAUGCAUGAGGGUUGGAAGAGUCUGGGCUGUUUUUAGACCUUCUGGUCAGCUGUAUUUGUGUAACAACUUUUGUAAUAAAUAGAAAAACCCUCUGCUCUGAUCAGUUCUUGUACUUUGACCUCUGCUAAGACAAGAGCAUGGCUGCCUCCUCUGAGCCCUAGGAGAAUCACAGCUUUAUGCCUGAUUGAAUACACCAUAGUGAGUAGGACAGCUCAUGACACAGGUCAGCCUGGCUGCCUCCGGCUCCUUACUGUCAUUUGCUCAUUCCUCUUGUAUUCUUGAAGUCAAAUCUUCUUUUUUCUCACCUUCAAGAGUCUGCGUUCACAACUAAACACUAAGUGCCCUUUCUUAUUUCCUCCUAAAGAAGAAACAGAUUCUUGAGAGAGCAGAGACAAAAAAAUAGAACUAGGCAGCAUAGAUGAAACAACUGCAUGACAUGGGAAGAAGACAACUAAACCCCGAGGAGAAUGCACUGGAAUGGACAGUUGCUCUUAAACCCUACCCAGAGGGCCUCCCCCAGCUGGACCCUCAUACACAGUGUGUGUAUCCAAAAGGCCAUUGCUAUUUCAGCAAAUAUUUGUUGAGUACUUCUCCAUGCCGGACACUUGGGAAAGAGAAAUGAACGACACAGGCAAUGCCCCUGCCCUGUGGGCCUUAUAUUAUAGUCAAGGUAACAGAAUCAACAAGCCAACACAAAAAUAAAGAACUUCAAAUAGGGAUAAGAACUCUAACAAACACAAGGUAUUUUGGUCAAGAAGGAAUGUGGGGUGGGCAGUGGGGAACGUAACUUAAAUUAGAUCAUCAGAAAGUCCUCCCUGAGGAGAUGGGAUUUUUUUGUUUUUUAGAGACAGGGUUUCACUCUGUCACCCAGGCUGGAGUGCAGUGGCACAAUCACACCUCACUGCAGCCUCAACUUCCUGGGCUCAAGUGAUCCUCCUGCAUCAGCUUCCCAAGUAGCUGGGACUACAAGUGUGUACCACCACAUCCAGCUAACAUUUUUGGGGGUGGGAAGAGAUGGGGUCUUACUAUGUUGUCCAGGCUAAGAGGUGGGAUUUGAGCUGAGACUUGAAUGCCCAGGAGUUAAAUGUCUUAAGAUAUGGAGCAGGCCGUUAGAAAGGAGGGAGCAGCAACUGGAAGGUAGAAUAGUCUUAUUCAAGGAAUAAGAACUAUGUAAUCACAGCAUGGUGAAGAGUUAGGAAGUG